AUUCUGCGCCUGCUGCGCCCCCUCGGCCACCUGCGGGGACAGCCCCUGCCUCAGCCGAGAAGGGGAGCAGAAGGGUUGCGCCCCGCGCCAGCGGUGAGGGGCCGAACGGAAGGAGGUCAGGGCUGGUUUCCCCCCACCCGCCGAAGGGAGGCGUCUGGCAGCCUCACUGACACCUUAUCCUGUCCCGGGAGCGAACCUGAACCCGCGGGAGCCUCUCGCCCCGCGCGGGCCCAGGAGAGAGGGAUCUGGCGGGGCAGCCCGCGGGAGGCAGGGGAGGGGUCCAUCCCGGAGCCCUCUGCUCUGUGCGUCGACCCUGCCGGGGUUGCCGCUCAGAUAACGGGCCCGAGGCGUGGGAACCGGCCCGCCAGGCCUGCGCUUUUCGCCGCGCGCCUCGGAGAGGACGGGGGUGCGGGGCGGCGGGCAGGCGGCAGGGAGGGGCGCACCCGGGAGCGCACCCGCCGCCCGCCCUCCCUGCGCUGCUGCCCCGCUGCUGGGCCAGACUCCAGCGGGCCCGCCUGGCAUUUCACAGGCCAAAAUCGAACAGAACCCCGAGUUUGCCAGCUCUUGCCCCUGUUCUUUGCUUCUCGUUUUGUUGGUGAAGAUAUCACAGUGAUGUCUGCAUUCAACCUGCUGCAUUUGGUGACAAAGAGCCAGCCAGUAGCCCUUCGAGCCUGUGGGCUUCCCUCAGGGUCGUGUAGGGAUAAAAAGAACUGUAAGGUGGUCUUUUCCCAGCAGGAACUGAGGAAGCGGCUAACACCCCUGCAGUACCAUGUCACUCAGGAGAAAGGGACCGAAAGUGCCUUUGAAGGAGAAUACACACAUCACAAAGAUCCUGGAAUAUAUAAAUGUGUUGUUUGUGGAACUCCAUUGUUUAAGUCAGAAACCAAAUUUGACUCCGGUUCAGGUUGGCCUUCAUUCCACGAUGUGAUCAAUUCUGAGGCAAUCACAUUCACAGAUGACUUUUCCUAUGGGAUGCACAGGGUGGAAACAAGCUGCUCUCAGUGUGGUGCUCACCUUGGGCACAUUUUUGAUGAUGGGCCUCGUCCAACUGGGAAAAGAUACUGCAUAAAUUCGGCUGCCUUGUCUUUUACACCUGCGGAUAGCAGUGGCACCGCCGAGGGAGGCAGUGGGGUCGCCAGCCCGGCCCAGGCAGACAAAGCGGAGCUCUAGAGUAAUGGAGAGUGAUGGAAACAAAGUGUACUUAAUGCACAGCUUAUUAAAAAAAUCAAAAUUGUUAUCUUAAUAGAUAUAUUUUUUCAAAAACUAUAAGGGCAGUUUUGUGCUAUUGAUAUUUUUUCUUCUUUUGCUUAAACAGAAGCCCUGGCCAUCCAUGUAUUUUGCAAUUGACUAGAUCAAGAACUGUUUAUAGCUUUAGCAAAUGGAGACAGCUUUGUGAAACUUCUUCACAAGCCACUUAUACCCUUUGGCAUUCUUUUCUUUGAGCACAUGGCUUCUUUUGCAGUUUUUCCCCCUUUGAUUCAGAAGCAGAGGGUUCAUGGUCUUCAAACAUGAAAAUAGAGAUCUCCUCUGCAGUGUAGAGACCAGAGCUGGGCAGUGCAGGGCAUGGAGACCUGCAAGACACAUGGCCUUGAGGCCUUUGCACAGACCCACCUAAGAUAAGGUUGGAGUGAUGUUUUAAUGAGACUGUUCAGCUUUGUGGAAAGUUUGAGCUAAGGUCAUUUUUUUUUUUCUCACUGAAAGGGUGUGAAGGUCUAAAGUCUUUCCUUAUGUUAAAUUGUUGCCAGAUCCAAAGGGGCAUACUGAGUGUUGUGGCAGAGAAGUAAACAUUACCACACUGUUAGGCCUUUAUUUUAUUUUAUUUUCCAUCGAAAGCAUUGGAGGCCCAGUGCAAUGGCUCACGCCUGUGAUCCCAGCACUUUGGGAGGCCAAGGCGGGUGGAUCACGAGGUCAGGAGAUGGAGACCAUCCUGGCUAACAUGGUGAAACCCCGUCUCUACUAAAAAUACGAAAAAUUAGCCAGGCGUGGUGGUGGGCACCUGUAGUCCCAGCUACUCAGGAGGCUGAGGCAGGAGAAUGGCGUGAACCCGGAAGGCGGAGCUUGCAGUUAGCCGAGAUCAUGCCACUGCACUCCAGCCUACAUGACAAUGUGACACUCCAUCUCAAAAAAUAAUAAUAAUAACAAUAUAAGAACUAGCUGGGCAUGGUGGCGCAUGCAUGUAGUCCCAGCUACUCCUGAGGCUCAGUCAGGAGAAUCGCUUGAACUUGGGAGGCGGAGGUUGCAGUGAGCUGAGCUCAUACCACUGCACUCCAGCCUGAACAGAGUGAGAUCCUGUCAAAAAAGAAAAGAAAAAGAAAGCAGCAUUCAAAUGUAAGACAACUGUAAAAUAUUGAGCCCCACUUGGUCUAAAAUUCAAAAAGAAGAACGCCUGUCCAUCGCCUUUUUAUAAGUCCUUCUCUCCACACCUAAAAGCAGCUGCAGCUGGAAGGGCACAAAUUCCACUGUGUAAAAUAAAAUAUUAGGGGCAACACACUUCAUCAAGGCAGCAGGAAUGAGAGAGAGCAGAGAAGAUCAAGGAUGAAGUCUUGGGUACUGAAAAAUUCAGUGCUGGGCAGAAAAACUGACAGGGCAGUACAAGUAACAAACAGAAUCCAAGUGGGGUGGCCCUUGUGCACAGAGCUCCAGGUGACCUCUGGAGAGACAUGGGCAUUCACAUGGAAAGCUAAAACGGAAGCUCAAGUUUCAUACUCAACAUAAUCUUCUGUGUGACAAAGGACAAGCCAUGUAGCCUCUCUGUGCCUAUUUCUUCAUGCAUAAACUGGGACUCAUAAUAUUUGUAAAAUGUAUUGAUACUCUCAGGGCAAAUUCACUAUAUUGCUAUACAGUUGAGAUCAGUGUUGUAAAAUUAAACUGAUCUGGUUCUAAUUGCCUCAAAGGCCAAAGCCCAGGCAUUUGAAAUGGAAAGAAGCAGAGAGGAGGCUGACUUAGCUGAUUGGUAUGGAAACAGUUGGGCCAAGAGCCAGAAUUUCCCUUUGUAGCAACACGGCUAGUUUUACUUUGAGAAGCUCUGCUCAGCUGCUUUAUAACAUUAAGUCUGGCGGAAUGGAUGUCACUGUGCACAAUAAAGUUUUCACAAGUAUAAACAAUGGUGAUGUAAGUCAACAUUGCUGUAGCCAGGUGUGAAGGUUGUAUGGUGUGUGACGAAUGUACAUCAUGUUUGUAGGUUUGGAUGCUAAUCUUGAAUUGUAGUUUAAAAAAUACGUAUUUUUGUAACUCUUUGAAAGUUUAUGAAGACUGACAGCUUUCCUUGUAAGCACUAAGAGAAAAAAAAGAAAGAGGGACAUUUGACAAUUUUAAAGAAACAACAAGAAAUUAGAAUGAAAAUCUGUGACAAACAGCGUCAGUGUGGCCAUGUCCACAUUCCUACAUGUCUCUCUCUACAAGCACCUCUCUAAGAAGCCUGACAUCCCGGUGGACUCUUUAUAGUCAUGUACACUUGAUUCCAGAUGAGCUCUGGUCUUAUCUGGAUGCUCAGAUAAGAGGUUUCUAUCUGAGCAUCCAGAUGUUCCCUCAGGUUCCAAGACAUUUCACCCCAGGCCCUGGGUUCACUCUGGAAUUCGUAGGCUUCACGUCUCUCUAGAAAUGACGUGUAAAAUUUAAGACCAGACCUCAGCCAUCAGCGUCCAGACCAUCCUAGAAGUCUUUCCCAAUCUCACAGAGAAAGCCCUAGUAUUUCCCAGUGACCCCAGGAUUCCACGUUGGGGUGGCCAAAGAAAUAGGUCUCUCAGGGCUUUGCCACAGCCUCCAGCCCAUCCUUCAGAGGCACACACAGCACCUCUCGGCUGCUCCAGCUCUGUAGGAUAGCCUCCCCUGGGGUCCGUGGGACGCGGGCCACAGUGUUGAGGUAGACAAGGAGGAUCAGUGAGAGGCCUCUUCCCUCUCCACAGAGACUGGAUUGUCAUUGUUCCUUCAUUUAUAUCGUAGGGCUUAACAUUUCACUCAAAAAAAAGCCCCUCUUUUUCUAAUCCUUAGUCUUUGUUUCAAGGAAAGCCAGUUUUUCUUCUACCACAUUUUCCAGGAUCGACUUUAAGAAAAAUGCAACAUCUAUUGAAAAAAAGUGGGGUGUAUGCAUGUGGUUUAAUUCCAGAUUGCUUUUGGGUUUAAGUGGUAUCAAAUUUCAGUAUAUUUCUGUCUUAUGUGAAAGAAAUAUAUUACUAAAACGUCAGUGAGCAAUAAUGUCAGCUGUCAAGCACUAGAUUUAUUUUUGCAGGAUAUGGAGUGCAAUGAACUGAGUCAAUAUGGCAAGGUGUAUGUGAUCUGUGGGAGUUAUGCCAUUUAACAUAGGAAGUGCAUGGGACUUUCCCUCUCUGCACUCCAGCUCUUACUGUACCAUUAGAAGAUGCAGAAUUCUGUUGGUGUGCAAAAAGUAUAGCCUUACAUUCAAGCAGAAUGGAUCUGAAGAAAGCAGCAAUAUCUGUUACUAGAGAACAUUCCCAUGUGUUUAAACUCUUCACUUCUUAGAUGCAUUUAAAUUCUUAAUGCAAAUGACGUAGCAAUUUGAAAACUUCUCCGUAUUACUUGUGUUUAAAAUGUCUUGCUUUAAAUACAAAACAAAUGGUAAAGGGGAUUAUCUUUUGUUUAGAUGGUUAAAUAUUAUUUUUGCCUUAGAUAGCUUUGUAAUAAUUUUUCUCCAGACAGUUCAACACUUUUGAAAAAUGACAUGAAUUUUCAUUAAAAACCCUUUUCCUAUGUUUAUUGUAUACAAGAAUUAUGCAAUAAAAUUUCUUUAUAAAAAUA